CAUUUUGUCCCAGUCAGUCCGGAGGCUGCGGCUGCAGAAGUACCGCCUGCGGAGUAACUGCAAAGAUGCUGUCCGUGCGCGUUGCUGCGGCCGUGGUCCGCGCCCUUCCUCGGCGGGCCGGACUGGUGAGCACCGAAGGCCGGCAUGAUGCAGGCGGCCGGGUGGGGCUGCAGGGUGGUGGUGCGCCGGCUCGGGCGCUCUCUGCAGGAGGGCGAGGGGCUGUGGCGAAUGCCGCCAUCUUGCACCCGUGGCUUCUCCGGCUGGACAGAGCAGGCGACACAGGUGCCCUUUUGCUCGUCACCUGCGCAGAGGCAGAAUGGUACAGGGCAGACAGUUAACUCGAUGGUGUCCAGAGACAGGGCCUCAAGAUUCCUGUCUUCGGCUGACAGCGGCCCUAGAAGGGGGAUCUUGGGUGAAGGUCAGGGCUUGGGCGCUAGCUCUCCGAGGCCUGUUCUGAAUCGGUCUCCAGAAAUGCUUUGGGUUCAUCUUUCAUUGCUGCAAGGAACUUCCAUGCCUCUAACACUCAUCUUCAAAAGACUGGGACUGCUGAGAUGUCCUCUAUUCUUGAAGAGCGUAUUCUUGGAGCUGAUACCUCUGUUGAUCUUGAAGAAACUGGGCGUGUCUUAAGUAUUGGUGAUGGUAUUGCCCGCGUACAUGGGCUGAGGAAUGUUCAAGCAGAAGAAAUGGUAGAGUUUUCUUCAGGCUUAAAGGGUAUGUCCUUGAACUUGGAACCUGACAAUGUUGGUGUUGUCGUGUUUGGAAAUGAUAAACUAAUUAAGGAAGGAGAUAUAGUGAAGAGGACAGGAGCCAUUGUGGACGUUCCAGUUGGUGAGGAGCUGUUGGGUCGUGUAGUUGAUGCCCUUGGUAAUGCUAUUGAUGGAAAGGGUCCAAUUGGUUCCAAGACGCGUAGGCGAGUUGGUCUGAAAGCCCCCGGUAUCAUUCCUCGAAUUUCAGUGCGGGAACCAAUGCAGACUGGCAUUAAGGCUGUGGAUAGCUUGGUGCCAAUUGGUCGUGGUCAGCGUGAACUGAUUAUUGGUGACCGACAGACUGGGAAAACCUCAAUUGCUAUUGACACAAUCAUUAACCAGAAACGUUUCAAUGAUGGAUCUGAUGAAAAGAAGAAGCUGUACUGUAUUUAUGUUGCUAUUGGUCAAAAGAGAUCCACUGUUGCCCAGUUGGUGAAGAGACUUACAGAUGCAGAUGCCAUGAAGUACACCAUUGUGGUGUCGGCUACGGCCUCGGAUGCUGCCCCACUUCAGUACCUGGCUCCUUACUCUGGCUGUUCCAUGGGAGAGUAUUUUAGAGACAAUGGCAAACAUGCUUUGAUCAUCUAUGACGACUUAUCCAAACAGGCUGUUGCUUACCGUCAGAUGUCUCUGUUGCUCCGCCGACCCCCUGGUCGUGAGGCCUAUCCUGGUGAUGUGUUCUACCUACACUCCCGGUUGCUGGAGAGAGCAGCCAAAAUGAACGAUGCUUUUGGUGGUGGCUCCUUGACUGCUUUGCCAGUCAUAGAAACACAGGCUGGUGAUGUGUCUGCUUACAUUCCAACAAAUGUCAUUUCCAUCACUGACGGACAGAUCUUCUUGGAAACAGAAUUGUUCUACAAAGGUAUCCGCCCUGCAAUUAACGUUGGUCUGUCUGUAUCUCGUGUCGGAUCCGCUGCCCAAACCAGGGCUAUGAAGCAGGUAGCAGGUACCAUGAAGCUGGAAUUGGCUCAGUAUCGUGAGGUUGCUGCUUUUGCCCAGUUCGGUUCUGACCUCGAUGCUGCCACUCAACAACUUUUGAGUCGUGGCGUGCGUCUAACUGAGUUGCUGAAGCAAGGACAGUAUUCUCCCAUGGCUAUUGAAGAACAAGUGGCUGUUAUCUAUGCGGGUGUAAGGGGAUAUCUUGAUAAACUGGAGCCCAGCAAGAUUACAAAGUUUGAGAAUGCUUUCUUGUCUCAUGUCGUCAGCCAGCACCAAGCCUUGUUGGGCACUAUCAGGGCUGAUGGAAAGAUCUCAGAACAAUCAGAUGCAAAGCUGAAAGAGAUUGUAACAAAUUUCUUGGCUGGAUUUGAAGCUUAAACUCCUGUGGAUUCACAUCAAAUACCAGUUCAGUUUUGUCAUUGUUCUAGUAAAUUAGUUCCAUUUGUAAAAGGGUUACUCUCAUACUCCUUAUGUACAGAAAUCACAUGAAAAAUAAAGGUUCCAUAAUGCAUAGUUGUUUUCUGUCAUUUGUGUUAUUCUUUAAAACCAAGAUCAAAUUGAGAAAUUGGUAAGCAAAUGCUUCUUGAUCUAUUUUACUUGAAUAUUGGUACAGUCAACUGGGCUAGAUAAUUCAAGGCUGAGCUCUUUGUAAGUUUUUUUUUUGUUUUUUUUUUUGAGACUGAUUCUCACUCUGUCACUGAGGCUGGAGUGCAGUGGCACCCUGUCGGCCCACUGCAACCUCCGUCUCCGGGUUCAAGCAAUUCUCUUGCCUCAGCCUCCCACGUAGCUGGGAUUACAGGUGCCCACCACCACGCCUGGCUAGUUUUUUAGUAUUUUUAGUAGAGACGGGGUUUCACCAUGUUGGCCAGGCCGGUCACGAACUCCUGACCUCAGGUGAUCCACCUGCCUUGGCCUACCUACCACAGUGCUGGGAUUACAGGUGUGAGCCACCGCACCCGGCUGCUCUUUGUAAGUUUCUAGAGUACUUUGUGUUUAAGAGAAAUUCCUAAACUGGAUAUAUGUGGCAGGCUGACAAUACUGAAGAGCAUAGCUGGCUUCUCUGCCCAGAGGAUGUACCUGCAUAAAGAGGUACUGUAGGCAGGAAAAUAAUAGGACAGUUAAAAUUCUCAGGGAAAUGAAAAAAUUGCUGGAACAAAAGCUGAGAAGAUAGAAUGCAUAGGAUUAUGAAAACUUGUCAAUAUCUCUUUUGUUUGUUUUGUGACAGGGUCUCCAUCUCUCUCACCCAGGCUGGAGUACAGUGGUGUGAUCUCAGCUCACUGCAGCUUCUGCCACCUGGGUUCAAUUGAUUCUUCCACCUCAGCCUCCUGAGUAGCUGGGGUUACAGGCACAUACCACCACGCCCAGCCAAUUUUUCUACUUUUUGUAGAGGGAGGGUCUUGCCAUGUUGUCCAGGCUGAUGAUGAACUCCUUGGCUCAAGUGAUCCUCCUGCCUUGGUCUCCCAAAGUGCUGGGAUUACAGGUGUGAACUACCAUGCCCGGCCAUCUUUUAAUAUUUUCACAGCUACUUUAUUUCCUCUGUUACUAGCUUUUCAUAGCCUUUGCUCAUUCUUACUGCAUUAAAUUUUUUUUACUGAUUUAUUUAUUUUUUUGAGACAGAGUCUUGCUCUGUCACCUAGGCUGGAGAGCAGUGGCGUAAUCUCAGCUCACUGCACCUUUCACCUCCUGGGUUCAAGCGAUUCUCCUGCCUUAGCCUCCCAAUUAGCUGGGACCACAGGCCCAUGCCACCACACCCGGCUAACAUUUUGUAUUUUUAGUAGAGACAAGGUUUCACCAUGUUGGCCAUGCUGCUCUUGAGCUCCUGACCUCGUGGUCUGCCCGCCUCAGCUUCCCAAAGUGCUGGGAUUACAGGUGUGAGCCACCACGCCCAGCCUACUGAUUUAUUUAUUUACUUUUAAUUUUUCAUAGCCUUUGCUCAUUCUUAAUGUGUUACCUUUUUUUUUACUUAGUUAUUUAUUUAUUUGAGAUGGAGUCUCCGUCGUCCAGGCUGGAGUGCAGUGACCUGAUCUUGGCUCACUGCAACCUCUGCCUCCAGGUUCAAGCAAUUCUCCUGCCUCAGCCUCCCGAGAAGCUGGAACUACAGGCACCCACCACCAUGCCCUGCUAAUUUUUGUAUUUUUAGUAGAGGCGGGGUUUCACCAUAUUGGCCAGGCUGGUCUCGAACUCCUGACCUUGUGAUCUGCCUGCCUUGGCCUCCCACAGUGCUGGGAUUACAGGUGUGAGCCACCACACCUGGCCUUUUUUUUUUUUUUUUGAGACGGAGUCUCACUGUCUCCCAGGCUGGAGUGCAGUGGUGCGAUGUCGGCUCACUGCAAGCUCUGCCCCCUGGGUUUGCGCCGUUCUCCUGCCUCAGCCUCCCGAUUAGCUGGUACUACAGGCGCCUGCCAUCACGCCCAGCUAAUUUUUUUUUUUUUGUAUUUUUAGUAGAGACGGGGUUUCACCAUGUUCGCCAGGAUGGUCUCGAUCUCCUGACCUCAUGAUCCACUUACCUCGGCCUCCCAAAGUGCUGGGAUUACAGGCUUGAGCCACCGCGCCCGGCCUCUUUUUUUUUUUUUUUUUUUUACUGAUAUAUAAAGGCUUUUGUCUGUAAGGGUCAUACAUGGUCAUGUUCUAAAAUAUUUUUCCUAGGGUUCCCCCUUCCUUGCCAUUUUAUUUUGUUGAUGGGGAUUUGCUGUACCGAAACUUCAUUCUUAUCCAUCUCUCUGUCUCCAGUAAGUCAAAAUAUAUUUACAUAUGUGGGCUCCAAUAUCUUUGGUAGGAAAAGGAGAGUUCUUAAAGUACUCAUAAGUCCUUUUCAGUACUUAGAGGAACACUAAACUUGAUAGCAGUUGGUCAUUUCUGAUCAACUCUUGCUUUCUAGCUACUUGAGAAAUAACUUCUAGAUCUGAUUUUCCUUUUCUGAAAUAAGGAAGUUACUUUUAGUUAGAAGGUUCUGCACAUUUCGUUUUUUUUUUUUUUUUUUUUUUUUGUUUUUUUUUUUUGAGAGUUUUGCUCUUGUUGCCCAGGCUGGAGUGCAAUGGCACGAUCUCGGCUCACCACAACCACCGCCUCCUGGGGUCAAGCAAUUCUCCUGCCUCAGGCUCCUGAGUAGCUGGGAUUACAGGCAUGCACCACCACGCCUGGCUAAUUUUGUAUUUUUAGUAGAGAUGGGGUUUCUCCAUGUUGGUCAGGCUGGUCUCAAACUCCUGACCUUAGGUGGUCCACCGGCCUCCCAAAGUACUGGGAUUACAGGGGUGAGCCACUGCGCCCGGCUUGUUGGAGCAUUUUAUACCUAGUGUCAGUGGUGAUUACUACUUUGGAGAAAAAUACUUUGGCUAAUGGAUUGGAAUUAAUUUAUUACUGGGAGUAUGUAUUGUUUGUUUGUUGACUGGAUCUCGUAGCCCACUCCUGGCACGUAAAUGCUCAAUAAACUUCUCAAAUGAAGACAACCAUGUUUGUCCAUUAUAAAUCAAAUUCCAAAUGUUAACUACUGGUCUGGUCUGAUGAGAUUUUUUUUUUUUUUUUUUUUUUUGAGACGGAGUUUUGUUUUUGUUGCCCAGGCUGGAGUGCAAUGGCGCGAUCUCGGCUCACUGCAACCUCCACCUCCUGGGUUCAAGUGAUUCUCCUACCUCAGCCUCCUGAGUAGCUGUGAUUAUAGGUGUGCACCACCAUGCCUGGCUAAUUUUUGUAUUUUUAGUAGAGACGGGGUUUCACCAUGUUGGCCAGGCUGGUUUCGAACUCCUGACCUUAGAUGAUCCACGUGCCUCGACCUCCUAAAGUGCUGGGAUUACAGGCGUGAGCCACUGUGCCUGGCCCACGCCAGGCACAGUGAUAUUUAAAAAUGUGAUUUUUAAAUAUCACAUUUAAAAAUAUGUGAUAUUUUUAAAGAAUAUGAUAGCCCAGGCGCAGUGGCUUACGCCUGUAAUCUCAGCACUUUGGGACGAUCACUUGAGCCCAGGAGUUUGAAACAGGCUGCAGUCAGCUAUGAUCACGCCACUGCACUCCAGCCUAGGUGACAGAGACCCUGACUCUUAAAAAAAGUUGUGCUAGAAGACUUCAAGAUCUCCCCUAAAACUGUAUAGUCCUUUCCCUGGUGUUUUUGCUGAGCUAUAGAGUCCAGCCCUUUCUGUUACAGCAAUGAACCAUGAGAUUCAAAUACUGCUUUUUACUAAGUACUUACAGACUAAUGACAUAGGAGACCUCAUAGGCACCUGGCUGUUUUUAACCAGGCAGGCCUAAAUACACUGCCCAAGUGGCCCUUCUGUGUGGCAACAAAAUGGCUGUCAUAAAAUUGUGUCUGUGUGCAUUUAUCUUAUCACUGGGGGUGGUGAACAUUUGAGAAGGCACUUGACCUUUGAAAUGUGAAGUUUUAUGGAUUUCAGACUUGUAUUUUAAAAACUAUUUGUUAACUGUAA